AGCCGCUGUUCUGCCCCGCGGGGGCAUCCGCUGGGUCCCCGCGCCGUUGUCAAGACCGGGGACCUGGACGCAGCGGAGAGAGGUGCCGCCGCCCGCCCCGUCCAGUCGCCGCGCGCAGGCACUGCAGUCAGCGGUGAACUGACUUCAUCCCAAUCCCUCAGCCCCCACCAGGACCAGUCUGGAGUCCCUCCCCUGCCCCCAUUGAAAUUUCCCUUCCGUCCCCAAACUUACCUCUGAUCUAGACCUUACUCACCUCCUUCCUGUUUCCUAAGACUCCUUCCUGCCGUCCACAGACCGAGCCUUUUAUCUUUGUCCACCCUGUGCCAGACACCUCCUUUUCCAGAACCUUCUCCUUACUGGUGACCUUACUUAUCUCUGUUGCUUUCUGGGGUCCUAGGAAAUGCCAGCACUCCCACCCACAUUGCCUGAACUUUCCAACACUCCCUAACUGCGCUGUGUCCUAUCUCAACACUUUCUCAUGUAUUUCUUGUGUCUUCUAGAACAUUCCCCCGCCAUUAUUACUUCAAUAUGGCUACACAUACUUCCUAAUUGCCCUGCAAACCAUCUCCUUCUCACCAUUGCCCAGCGAUGCUUUCGUCUCCUCCAUAAACACUCCCGGAGACCAAUUUUUGUGUCACCCCCAUACUCCCUCGUUGACACACUGACUCCAUACAUAACCUCCUUGAAAAACCUCUUUAUUAAUCUCACCAUCCUCCAGACUUCCCUCCUGUCAUAAUUCCAUCCCUCCUCCAACUUUUCCCUCUCAAGCUCUGCCCUUCCCAGCCCAGCCCAGCCUACCCAACCUCAUCUCUUCCCUGUAGACCACAUCCCACCAUGUUCCCCUGAGCCUCCAAGGAAGGGGCUCAGGGGGCCCCAUGGCCUCCCGCUCCCUGUGGCCCCACAGCCCCCGUGGGCCAGGGGAAGCGCCCCAGAAGCCGAAGUGCCCACCAUGGGCAACCACACGUGGGAGGGCUGCCACGUGGACUCGCGCGUGGACCACCUCUUUCCGCCAUCCCUCUACAUCUUUGUCAUCGGCGUGGGGCUGCCCACCAACUGCCUGGCUCUGUGGGCGGCCUACCGCCAGGUGCAACAGCGCAACGAGCUGGGCGUCUACCUGAUGAACCUCAGCAUCGCCGACCUGCUGUACAUCUGCACGCUGCCGCUGUGGGUGGACUACUUCCUGCACCACGACAACUGGAUCCACGGCCCCGGGUCCUGCAAGCUCUUUGGGUUCAUCUUCUACACCAAUAUCUACAUCAGCAUCGCCUUCCUGUGCUGCAUCUCGGUGGACCGCUACCUGGCUGUGGCCCACCCACUCCGCUUCGCCCGCCUGCGCCGCGUCAAGACCGCCGUGGCCGUGAGCUCCGUGGUCUGGGCCACGGAGCUGGGCGCCAACUCGGCGCCCCUGUUCCAUGACGAGCUCUUCCGAGACCGCUACAACCACACCUUCUGCUUUGAGAAGUUCCCCAUGGAAGGCUGGGUGGCCUGGAUGAACCUCUAUCGGGUGUUCGUGGGCUUCCUCUUCCCGUGGGCGCUCAUGCUGCUGUCGUACCGGGGCAUCCUGCGGGCCGUGCGGGGCAGCGUGUCCACCGAGCGCCAGGAGAAGGCCAAGAUCAAGCGGCUGGCCCUCAGCCUCAUCGCCAUCGUGCUGGUCUGCUUUGCGCCCUAUCACGUGCUCUUGCUGUCCCGCAGCGCCAUCUACCUGGGCCGCCCCUGGGACUGCGGCUUCGAGGAGCGCGUCUUUUCUGCAUACCACAGCUCACUGGCUUUCACCAGCCUCAACUGUGUGGCGGACCCCAUCCUCUACUGCCUGGUCAACGAGGGCGCCCGCAGCGAUGUGGCCAAGGCCCUGCACAACCUGCUCCGCUUUCUGGCCAGCGACAAGCCCCAGGAGAUGGCCAAUGCCUCGCUCACCCUGGAGACCCCACUCACCUCCAAGAGGAACAGCACAGCCAAAGCCAUGACUGGCAGCUGGGCGGCCACUCCGCCCUCCCAGGGGGACCAGGUGCAGCUGAAGAUGCUGCCGCCAGCACAAUGAACCCCGAGUGGCACAGAAUCCCCAGUUUUCCCCUCUCAUCCCACAGUCCCUUCUCUCCUGGUCUGGUGUAUGCAAAUUGUAUGGAAAAAGGGCUGUGUUAAUAUUCAUAAGAAUACAAGAACUUAGGAAGAGUGAGGUUGGUGUGUCACUGGUCAACCUUUGUGCUCCCAGAUCCCAUCACAGUUUGGCGAUUGUGGAGGGCCUCCUGAAGGAGGAGAUGAGUAAAUAUAUUUUUUUGGAGACAGGGUCUCACUGUGUUGCCCAGGCUGGAGUGCAGUAGUGCAGUCGUGGCUCACUGCAGCCUCCACCUCCUGGGCUCUCCAGCGAUCUUCCCACAUCAGCCUCCCGAGUAGCUGGGACCACAAAUGUGAGCCACCAUGCCUGGCUAAUUUUUGUACUUUUUGUAGAAAUGGAGUCUCACUAUGUUUCCCAGGCUGAUCUUGAACUCCUGGGCUCAAGAGAUCCUCCUGCCUUGGCCUCCCAAAGUGCUCAGAUUAGAGAUGUGAGCCGCCAUGUCUGGCCAGAUAAAUUAAGUCAAACAUUUGGUUUCCAGAAAAUAAAGACAAAUAGAGAAGGUUAGAUUUUUUUUUUUCCAACAAGUGGAUAAAAGUCUGUGACUCGGGGGAAAGUGGAAGGAGAAAUGCAGCCGAUAUAGAGUCAUUAUGUUUGCAAAGCCCCUGGUCAUACAGGCCAGGGAACAUAAGACCGCAAUUCUAAGUUUCUAGAUAAACAGCGAUCUCCAAGUCAAGACUGAGGAUGAAGAGGGAGAAUGUCAGAACUCAAGUGAAGGGCAAUCAGGGCAGACUGCCUGGAGGAGUGAUGCCAGAAGGUUUGGGAAGAAGGUGUGGGACAAGAAGAAAGGGUAUUUAUUCAUUCAUUCAACAGAGGUUUAUGUAGGGCACUGUGCUGGGUGGGGCUGGGGACACAACAAUGACUGAGGCAGCCUGGCCUUGCCUUCACAGGGCUCACCAUACACAAGUAAAUAAAAAAUAUGUAAUGUUUGGAAUUGCUAAA